AGGGCCGUAGUAACCCAUUCAUGGGGCCCGCGCGCGGCUGCAGCCGGGCUCCGUGGCGCUCGCAGCCACCGCCUCCUCUCGGCUCCAGGUCUUCCCCUUCUUUUUACAACUGAUCCUGUUGGGGAUUUUUUUUUUUUCUAAAUUGGAACGGUGGGGAGGAGCAGGGAGGGGGGACCUGGAGGAAGGGGAGAGAUUAGGCAGCCAUCAAUUUCCUCCAGUUUCUCCCAGAACAGGUGAUGCUUCUAAAUUGUGAUCACUUUCAGGAGGCAGCACUGCAGCUGGAAGGAUGCGAGCGACCUAGGGUGGAGUGGCUGAGGCGGCAGAUCUGAACUUGCGGAGGAUAAGAACCCAAACUUUGACUACAUCAGUCCGCACCUCGCCAGUGAAGCAAAGGACGGGUUAUCUUUUUUUUUUUUCUAAGACUCAAACUUGGGCACUUGAUCCCUUUUCUUGGAUUGCUUUGGAGGAGACGAUUUGCUGGCAACGUUGGGAACAGUCAGGACUGUGUUGUAACUCUUACUUUUAAAGCGACAGUAGAGGAUCAGACUUUUUAAAUGUUUGGAAUUCAAGAUACUUUAGGAAGAGGACCAACUCUGAAAGAGAAAUCGCUGGGCGCGGAGAUGGAUUCGGUCAGGUCCUGGGUCCGGAAUGUCGGAGUGGUGGACGCUAAUGUCGCCGCGCAGAGCGGGGUCGCCCUGUCCCGGGCCCACUUUGAGAAACAGCCUCCUUCCAACUUGAGGAAAUCCAACUUCUUUCACUUCGUCCUGGCGCUCUAUGACAGGCAGGGCCAGCCGGUGGAGAUCGAGCGGACGGCCUUCGUGGACUUUGUGGAGAAUGACAAAGAACAAGGCAACGAGAAGACCAACAACGGCACUCACUACAAGUUACAGCUCCUCUACAGCAACGGUGUCCGCACGGAACAGGACCUCUAUGUCAGGCUCAUCGACUCGGUCACCAAGCAGCCCAUCGCUUACGAGGGACAGAAUAAGAAUCCGGAAAUGUGCCGAGUUCUCCUGACGCACGAAGUGAUGUGUAGUCGAUGCUGCGAAAAGAAAAGCUGUGGAAACCGAAAUGAGACUCCAUCGGACCCAGUCAUAAUUGACAGAUUCUUUUUAAAAUUUUUCCUCAAGUGCAAUCAGAAUUGUUUGAAAACAGCAGGAAACCCAAGGGACAUGAGACGGUUUCAGGUUGUGUUGUCAACAACGGUGAAUGUGGAUGGACACGUCCUGGCUGUUUCUGACAACAUGUUUGUUCAUAACAACUCCAAGCAUGGACGGAGAGCAAGAAGACUCGAUCCAUCGGAAGCUACCCCCUGCAUCAAAGCCAUUAGCCCGAGUGAAGGCUGGACCACAGGAGGAGCCAUGGUCAUCAUCAUCGGGGACAACUUCUUUGAUGGUCUCCAAGUGGUGUUUGGGACUAUGCUUGUAUGGAGCGAGCUAAUAACCCCUCAUGCCAUCAGAGUACAGACUCCUCCCCGGCACAUCCCAGGCGUGGUAGAGGUGACAUUAUCUUAUAAAUCUAAACAGUUCUGCAAAGGAGCCCCAGGAAGGUUCAUUUACACAGCAUUAAAUGAACCCACCAUAGACUAUGGCUUCCAGAGACUGCAGAAGGUCAUCCCUAGGCAUCCUGGAGAUCCUGAGAGAUUAGCUAAGGAGAUGCUGUUGAAAAGAGCUGCAGAUCUAGUGGAAGCUCUUUAUGGCACACCACACAAUAACCAGGACAUCAUUUUGAAGCGAGCCGCAGACAUUGCUGAAGCUCUCUACAGCGUCCCCAGGAAUCCCAGCCAGCUUCCAGCCCUCUCUAGCUCCCCAGCGCACAGUGGCAUGAUGGGAAUCAACUCCUAUGGCAGCCAGCUUGGGGUCAGCAUCUCAGAGUCAACACAAGGAAAUAAUCAAGGGUACAUCCGCAACACAAGCAGCAUCUCUCCGCGGGGAUACUCUUCCAGCUCCACGCCUCAACAGUCUAAUUACAGUACCUCCAGCAACAGUAUGAAUGGCUACAGCAAUGUCCCCAUGGCCAACUUGGGUGUUCCAGGUUCACCAGGAUUUCUAAAUGGCUCACCCACCGGCUCUCCUUAUGGAAUCAUGUCAUCAAGUCCCACCGUUGGGUCUUCCAGCACAUCCUCCAUCCUCCCAUUUUCCUCUUCAGUUUUUCCUGCUGUCAAACAGAAGAGUGCCUUUGCCCCUGUCAUCAGGCCCCAAGGCUCCCCUUCACCUGCCUGCUCCAGCGGCAAUGGAAAUGGAUUCAGAGCCAUGACCGGACUUGUUGUACCCCCGAUGUAAAGAAGAACUGCUUUCUUAUAGCACAAAACUACUUACUCUGAUGGACCAAUAAUGAAGAAAGCACUAGGAGCUCUUUUGGGGGUGUAGUGGUGCCCCCACAUGAACAUGAUGGACACCCUUGGGUCUGCAAGGAGCCAGCAUCUUACUUGGUCCCACGUCCUCCUAUAGCUCUGAUGGUGGCUACACAAACUGACCCUCUUGGGACAAGGACAAAAGAUGUCAUUGACGUAGUCAGUGCUAAGAGCAGAAAUGCAAUUCUUUGUUAUGAACAUUAUGAAAACCACCUUCCUAUGUUUGUAAAAUAUUUAAGAAAAAAUUGGCAAACAAUUAAUGCUUAAUAUUUUGGAUACUAUUUGUUUUUCUUUGUAGGAAAAAAAAGUUGAAAGUUUCUAUUUUCUAUGAAGCCUUUCAGAUACCAAUUUAGUUUAUGCAGAAAAAAAUUGAACAAAACAGGGUACCAGCACGGAAGACUUUCUUAAAACGCAACCUGAAUUGAAUGAUGAAAUGUUGUAUGUGUGUUUGCUUAUAGCUUAAUCUCUUUAAAAAAUGAACAAAAAAAGGGAAAAAUUUUAAAAUGUUUUACAAUUAUUUAAAUAAAUAAAUGUGUAACUUAUUGUAAGUAGAGGUAGAAAUUAAGACCUUUUUUUGGAAGAGAGAGGGAUUUCUCUUCCUGAUGUAAAAUGAAAAUGAUGCAAACAUGUAGUAACAAGUUUUAAAGGUGUGUGAUUAUUACUGCAGUUACUUACUAGAUUCUUAUCCCCUGUCCUGCACCCCCUCCUUUUCCAUCACUUUAUUGACCCAAGGGCAAGAACAUGUAGAUUCCCACAGAACACCCUAAUGCAGAAACAGACACUCUAGCACAUGCACAAAUACUCCAACCCAUCAAUUCAUUCCCAGCUCCGUCUGAUUUCUAAAUAGUCCACACUCUUGUGAAUACUUUUUAAAAUUCCUAUUAUUAGCUUUCAACGUUCUCCCCUGAGCAGUCCAGAGAAUUCCCAUGUUUGAGUCUGUCUCAGGCUUUCAGCAUCCCAAGGAAAGAAGCACCUCACCUUCUAGCAGAGCCAAAACCACAGACUUUCUUAACCAAGGGACCCCUUGGGAAUUCCUCCUCACCAGAACCCCACCACUCCCUCCGCUUUGGGUGCCUGGUUCAGUACAGAGGUACACAGCCCCAUAGAACUUCAGCAACACGGUUUGGAGAAGAUAACUCUGUUUGAUGGACUCUUUAGAGUCAGUCUUAGAACAUCCAAGUCCUUUCCUCUCCCUGUCAAUUUCCCCUUUUAUGGCAUUAAACUCUCUUGAAAAACAUAGCUAUGCCACUCGACAGUUUCUAGUCAAGAAUGAGACGGAAUGUGGGAGAGGGAUAUUAAAAGCCCUAAUCCCCUCUUCUGAUGUUCGAAGAAAGGCAAGACCAGAUUCUUGGGAGAUCCAGAGAUUAGGGGCAUCUGCGUUCUAUGCAGCACAGUUACCCAGCCCUUUGAUGGGCUCUUCAUCGUUUUGUGACUAGCUCUUAGAGGGGAAGAACCUUGCCUUAGCUGCUAACAGUGGUUGAUUCUUGAAAGCUUAUGUAAUCCUAGAGACAUAUCCAGGCAUAUUGGGAUUGCCAAUAAAGAUGUCACUUGUUUCCACGUUGGGGUUCUCCUUAUUGACUCAUGAGCACCACAAUAGAGUCUAUACACAGACUUAGUUUGGGGUUCUUGGUUGGGAUUUCAGCAUUAGAAAUAGAUGCAGCACUCAUGGAAAAACAUCAUGAGUGCAUCUGAGCCAAUUUUAGAUGAUUUCAUUAAUUCUGCAUACCUUCUCUUUGACCCAUUGAUGCAGGCCCACAUCUAUCCAGCCCCAACUGUCUUAUUUGCCUUUAACCCAUUCUGGAAUUACCCAGUAUGACUUAUAUUAUUUCUAUGCACAUGAGAAUCCAAGGUUUUAGAAACCUGGCAUGCUUAUAACUACUGCUGACAGUCCCUCAUAGUCAGGGCUUAAAGCGCCAAAAUACACGGAAACAUAAGAGAAAAAGUCCCCCAGUGAGAAACCUGAUUGAUGGAAGGGGAAGAAUGUGUGGAAUAUGAAUGUUACCUUCCAAAAGUGAAGGCAGAGCAAAAUUAAGCAUGUUUAGCCCUGGAUUUGAGCCAAUCCAACAUAAGGAAAUUUUGUUUUUUUUAAGUAGCAUUGCUUUUAGAACCUGUGAAUUUUCCUUUUGCAUGAAGAUGAGUGCAGUACUGUCUUCAAAAUGAUUGUAGAAUUUCUUGGUAGCUUUACACCGAAAAAUGCGUGUAACUAAAUACCAGACAUCUUGACCAUUCAGCUAGAACCCUGGCAGCAACAGAGCUAUUUAAUUGUACAAAUGUGUGUAAGGAUUAUUUUUAGUGUACUAAUAAAUUAAAAACAAAGCUACCCUGUCCUCGUUAGUCAUUGCUAUUCAAUCAUUCCAGUCCCAAGUUAUUUUUGUGCCACUUGGAAUAUGAGUAUUUCUAUUGGUAACUACAAACUCUAUCCUGUGUUUGUAAGAGGAGCUGUGUAAGAUUUUUUUCAUUUAAAGGGACAAUUUACUUCAUUAUUUAUCUUUCUUUUGUUAUAGCGUUGUAAUUCUUCUCAGUUUUUCUUUGCACAUUUCAAUAUGCAUGGUUUAAAAACCAUUAACUUCUCUACCUUUUGUACAGUAAGGUUUCAUUUUCACACUGUAUAGUUUCAUUUUAUUGUUUUGCUUUGUCAGUUAUAUACAGUAUAAAGUUGCUAUGCACAGAGCUUUUUGUAAAGACAGCUUUUUUGUUUACUGUUUUUAAUGGUCUUACUUAAAGAAUAUCUUGUUUGUAAAAUGAAUAUGUCUACUUCAGUUUUAAACUUUAAAUUAUCCUAACAAAAAAAUAAAAUUUUUGUACUGUAAAAA